CGCGGGUGGUUAGUUGAGCCGGCUCCGGCGGGGAAGGAGGCGGGCUGCGGCUGCGGCUGGGGCUGAAGCUGGGGCUGGGGUUGGGGGACUGCCCGGGGCUUAGAUGGCUCCGAGCCCGUUUGAGCGUGGUCUCGGACUGCUAACUGGACCAACGGCAACUGUCUGAUGAGUGCCAGCCCCAAACCGCGCGCUGCUCGGGACCUUAGAGCCUCUGACUCAGGCUGGAAGAUUUGAGAGCUGGAUUAAGUACUUGUUGGCUCACGCCCGUGACUGUUCCGCUGUUUAGCUCUUGUUUUUUGUGUGGACACUCCUAGGAUAGAAAGUUUGGUAUGUUGCUAUACCUUUGCUUCUCCCACCUUCCCCAAUAUCUAAUAUGUAUUUCUCAUUCUUAGAAUAAUCCAGAAUGGCUACUCUGAUCUAUGUUGAUAAGGAAAAUGGAGAACCAGGCACCCGUGUGGUUGCUAAGGAUGGGCUGAAGCUGGGGUCUGGACCUUCAAUCAAAGCCUUAGAUGGGAGAUCUCAAGUUUCAACACCACGUUUUGGCAAAACGUUCGAUGCCCCACCAGCCUUACCUAAAGCUACUAGAAAGGCUUUGGGAACUGUCAACAGAGCUACAGAAAAGUCUGUAAAGACCAAGGGACCCCUCAAACAAAAACAGCCAAGCUUUUCUGCCAAAAAGAUGACUGAGAAGACUGUUAAAGCAAAAAGCUCUGUUCCUGCCUCAGAUGAUGCCUAUCCAGAAAUAGAAAAAUUCUUUCCCUUCAAUCCUCUAGACUUUGAGAGUUUUGACCUGCCUGAAGAGCACCAGAUUGCGCACCUCCCCUUGAGUGGAGUGCCUCUCAUGAUCCUUGACGAGGAGAGAGAGCUUGAAAAGCUGUUUCAGCUGGGCCCCCCUUCACCUGUGAAGAUGCCCUCUCCACCAUGGGAAUCCAAUCUGUUGCAGUCUCCUUCAAGCAUUCUGUCGACCCUGGAUGUUGAAUUGCCACCUGUUUGCUGUGACAUAGAUAUUUAAAUUUCUUAGUGCUUCAGAGUUUGUGUGUAUUUGUAUUAAUAAAGCAUUCUUUAACAGAUUCUU